GCCCCCUUGCUUCGCGCGCGCGCAGCCCCGCAGCGCAGCUUUGGCGGCGCCAGCAGCGGAGCCAACGCACCCGAGUUUGUGUUUGAGGCCACCCUGAGGAUCGGGACAGCUGUUCCUUUGGGCUGCAGAAACUCCGCUGAGCAGAACUUGCCGCCAGAAUGCUCCUCCUGUUGCUGAGUAUCAUCGUCCUCCACGUCGCGGUGCUGGUGCUGCUGUUCGUCUCCACGAUCGUCAGCCAAUGGAUCGUGGGCAAUGGACACGCAACUGAUCUCUGGCAGAACUGUAGCACCUCUUCCUCAGGAAAUGUCCACCACUGUUUCUCAUCAUCACCAAACGAAUGGCUGCAGUCUGUCCAGGCCACCAUGAUCCUGUCGAUCAUCUUCAGCAUUCUGUCUCUGUUCCUGUUCUUCUGCCAACUCUUCACCCUCACCAAGGGGGGCAGGUUUUACAUCACUGGAAUCUUCCAAAUUCUUGCUGCCCUGCCUUCAUUAGAUAAGUCAGACAGAGCCCAAGAGACAACUUCAGUAUUUCUUAAAGACAAGAGUUAGCACUUUGGAGAUGCAAGCCGUGGAAGAGUGGGGCAAGAUAAUUAAGGAUCCUGGACCUCAAGGCAAAUAAAGUGUGUCCCCAGCAGAUCAAAACUGCUGUUUUCUGCAAUCAACAAUUAACCCGCAAUGAUUUCGCUCCUGACAUGGCCAUCUUUGCUGUCUUCUGAACUUCCUGUAGGUGGCAGGUCCUGGAUGCUGUCCCAUUUUGGUUCCAAGACUAUUGUGUGGCUCUCUUGACAGGGGCCAGUCAAGUGGCAGUUUUCUCCUCUGAGUUGCAGGAGGACAGGCUUAACAGGGUGGUUCAUGUGGCGUAUUCCCACUUCUGCACUGUCUUCAAACAAAGUUGCAGUGUCCAGUAAAACAGCAGCCCAAAUAGCAGUGAGGUUAGAUGUAGGUGGCCGGGCGGUGGGGGGGCGCGGGUGCAUUGGGAACUCUGGAACUGCAUGAAUCCCACACGGCAUACUGGAUUUAUAAUAGAGUCACUCAGAGCUUCUCAAAGACCCUGUUUUCAGGGAGGAAACAGACCAGGCUUUGUGCAGCUCCAGGCUGGGGUGCUGACAUCACUGGACCCCUCCUUGUGGGGGGACGCUGUCUGUCACGUGAGCUGGGGCCAUCAGUUUGAGCGUGGCUGCUCCACAGGGCCCAAGAUGGAGGCUUUUCUUCUCUUUCCAACACCGAAGGGCUGCAUUGGUGGGCCAGGGAGGGUGGCCUGACCCACCUGCAUAUCCAGUGCCCUUUAGCCUUCUUUGGGCUUCAAAUGCAACCUUGGGGCACCCAGGGAAAUGGAGCUUGCCUUUGAUCAUCUUCCCCCUCUGCAGCGUGGCUUCCCAGUCAUACUGUCGGCUGCAUCCUUAUUCCUCACUUUCUUUUUCCCUCUCCACACAUUUCUUUGUCUGUUUGGCAGUGCCCAUAGGCAUUGCUUGCUUCACCUGGUAUGUGGCAACUCUGUUAGGGGGACCAUAGGCCCCUGUGGUCUGCAUGGAGCUUAAUCCUUUUACCAUGGCGUGACUCCAAUAAUGGUAAAAUGUCACUUCACUUCCAUUGGCUUUAGGUAAUGCCACCACUCACUUGUAGAGUGGCAUAUAGAUUUCCAGGGGUUUCCAUACCCAACCACCCUUGGAAAGAGACAGGUAGGUUUUUCUUGCAGCCUGAAUGCCUGCUGGCCAUGUAGUGUGGCCUGGGAAUUGGUGACAGUGAAAGAAAGAGAAAUAGGGCAGAAAAUGUAAAGAAAACCCUCAGGUAUUAAGGCCUAGGUGGCCAAGAUUGGAAAUAGAGAGCAAGUUGUUUUCCUUGUUCCCAUAUUUUUGUGCUACCUCCUUUCAAUUCUGGACCUGGAAGCAGAUUUCCUUCCAGAGGUAGAAAUGUUCUUCCUACCCAGCAAUUGUCAGCAUCCGGGGUGGCGGAGAGGGGGCCGCUCUGCCAUGGACUCUCCGUCACCCAGCUUGUCCCUCUCCUUCCCCAGGUCUGUGCGUGAUGAGUGCUGCGGCCAUCUACACGGUGAGGCACCCGGAGUGGCAUCUCAACUCGGAUUACUCCUACGGUUUCGCCUACAUCCUGGCCUGGGUGGCCUUCCCCCUGGCCCUUCUCAGCGGUGUCAUCUAUGUGAUCUUGCGGAAACGCGAAUGAGGCGCCCAGACGGUCUGUCUGAGGCUCUGAGCGUACAUAGGGAAGGGAGGAAGGGAAAACAGAAAGCAGACAAAGAAAAAAGAGCUAGCCCAAAAUCCCAAACUCAAACCAAACCAAACAGAAAGCAGUGGAGGUGGGGGUUGCUGUUGAUUGAAGAUGUAUAUAAUAUCUCCGGUUUAUAAAACCUAUUUAUAACACUUUUUACAUAUAUGUACAUAGUAUUGUUUGCUUUUUAUGUUGACCAUCAGCCUCGUGUUGAGCCUUAAAGAAGUAGCUAAGGAACUUUACAUCCUAACAGUAUAAUCCAGCUCAGUAUUUUUGUUUUGUUUUUUGUUUGUUUGUUUUGUUUUACCCAGAAAUAAGAUAACUCCAUCUCGCCCCUUCCCUUUCAUCUGAAAGAAGAUACCUCCCUCCCAGUCCACCUCAUUUAGAAAACCAAAGUGUGGGUAGAAACCCCAAAUGUCCAAAAGCCCUUUUCUGGUGGGUGACCCAGUGCAUCCAACAGAAACAGCCGCUGCCCGAACCUCUGUGUGAAGCUUUACGCGCACACGGACAAAAUGCCCAAACUGGAGCCCUUGCAAAAACACGGCUUGUGGCAUUGGCAUACUUGCCCUUACAGGUGGAGUAUCUUCGUCACACAUCUAAAUGAGAAAUCAGUGACAACAAGUCUUUGAAAUGGUGCUAUGGAUUUACCAUUCCUUAUUAUCACUAAUCAUCUAAACAACUCACUGGAAAUCCAAUUAACAAUUUUACAACAUAAGAUAGAAUGGAGACCUGAAUAAUUCUGUGUAAUAUAAAUGGUUUAUAACUGCUUUUGUACCUAGCUAGGCUGCUAUUAUUACUAUAAUGAGUAAAUCAUAAAGCCUUCAUCACUCCCACAUUUUUCUUACGGUCGGAGCAUCAGAACAAGCGUCUAGACUCCUUGGGACCGUGAGUUCCUAGAGCUUGGCUGGGUCUAGGCUGUUCUGUGCCUCCAAGGACUGUCUGGCAAUGACUUGUAUUGGCCACCAACUGUAGAUGUAUAUAUGGUGCCCUUCUGAUGCUAAGACUCCAGACCUUUUGUUUUUGCUUUGCAUUUUCUGAUUUUAUACCAACUGUGUGGACUAAGAUGCAUUAAAAUAAACAUCAGAGUAACUCA